GCAGACAACGCGGCGGCGAUGUCCGCGAGCCAGGCGAGUGCCGCGGCGGCAGCGGCGGGGCCUUGCGCGCGGCAGGGCGGCCUGGGCUUCGGCCUCCCUCCGGUUCCCUGGAAGCGGGCCCGCGACCAGCGCGGGAGCAGCAGCAGAGGCGGAGGCUCCAGCGCGUCUCUCUCCUCCCCCUCAGCCUGAGCCGGGGGAAGCCAGGCGGCCCGGGUGUCUGGAGGGGGGGGGUCCGCUGCCCGAGAAUGGGAAUUCUCUUCACUAGAAUAUGGAGACUGUUCAAUCACCAGGAGCACAAAGUUAUCAUUGUUGGGCUGGAUAAUGCAGGGAAAACUACCAUUCUUUACCAAUUUUCUAUGAAUGAAGUUGUACAUACAUCUCCUACAAUAGGAAGUAAUGUAGAAGAGAUAGUGAUUAAUAAUACACGUUUCCUAAUGUGGGAUAUUGGUGGCCAAGAAUCUCUUCGUUCUUCCUGGAACACUUACUAUACUAACACAGAGUUUGUAAUAGUUGUUGUGGACAGUACAGACAGAGAGAGGAUUUCUGUAACUAGAGAAGAACUCUAUAAAAUGUUAGCGCAUGAGGACCUAAGAAAAGCUGGAUUGCUGAUUUUUGCUAAUAAACAAGAUGUUAAAGAAUGCAUGACUGUAGCAGAAAUCUCCCAGUUUUUGAAGCUAACUUCUAUUAAAGAUCACCAGUGGCAUAUCCAGGCAUGCUGUGCUCUAACUGGCGAGGGAUUGUGCCAAGGACUUGAAUGGAUGAUGUCACGACUUAAGAUUAGAUGAUCUCUACUGACCUCUUCUCAUAGAUUUUGUAUAAAUGAAGUGCUGGACUUUACCUGAAAGCUGCAAAAAUUAAUGGUUUAGAUAUAUUUAUAAUAAACUGAUUUAAACUUUUUCUAUAAGAAGAAAAAUUAAGACCACUUAUUUGAAAACAAAGAUGAAGUCUCACCUUCCAGUUUGCUUUCUCAUUAGUUUUUUCCAAAGUAAGUUAUUGAAGCUGUGAUUGACAUUUUUCUCAUAAUGAAUCCUCUCAGGACAUUGUGUAGCCUAUGGUAAGUACAAAGGGAGAGGAAGACAUUUUGAAUUUUAAGAGCUUUAUUAUCAGUUUAACCCUCCCUAGUUGAAUGUUAUUUUCUUCUUGUUCCAUUAAGUCAGAAUACAAAUCAGCACAGAUAUUCGAAUGUUUCCAAUAUUUUAAAAUGUAAUGUUACUUAUGAAAAGUAUUUUGCUUAAGGUUGUGUGUGUAUUGUGUAUAUACCUCAAGUUCAAGUUAAUGGCAUUGAUUUAUGUUCCAGACAAAAAUAACACAAAUAAUAAUAUCCUUCGUUAUAACCACAAUGAGAUAAGUAUUGGCAUUAGUGUUCAGUGCCAUUUUAUACUUUCUCUCUGUGUUCUCUGUAUUGUACUAACCAACCUCCCAAAUCGCUGAGCUGCUUGUUUAAAAAAAAAAAAAAGGAAAAGGAAAAAGCAUGACAUUGUGUAUCGAUUUUUUGUUGUUGACCAAAAUCACACACAUGGAAACAUGUAAUUCAACAGAGUGGGAAAGCUAGCAGAUUCUUGGCUUAGUAUUACUAAUAGGCAGGAUUGUACAAUGAGCAACUAUCAGAUUAUUCCUUUCAGUGGUUCUUAUGGCAUCUAAAUUACUGAAUAAAUUAUUAAUCCAUUAAUCAGUGAAUCAAAUUAUGAUUACAAUUAUCAAAUGAAUGCUCAGCAUUAAUUGAAAACUGUUUUGUGAAACAUGUCUACCCAGAAAAGUAGCAUUCUAUAAAUACUAUUAAACAACUUAGCUAUAUUAUUUUUAAGUAUUAAAUUAUAUGUCAAGCAGUUAAAGUGAAUUUCAGAGUAAAAGUAAGGCAUGUUUCUGAGCAACAUUGAUAAUUUCUUAAUUUGCAAAUUUCUUCUUAUUUUGGUACUUGGAAUAUAGUGUGAGAUUUUUUAUUUCUAAAUUUUGUUGUAUCUUCUAUUACAUAAAUGCAUUGACAAUUAUAAAAUGCAAGUGUUUUUUGAAUGAUUUUAAGAAUUUGGCUUAAAAAUUGAUUGAUACAACGUAUUAUUUGUACUAAGAAGUAACUUGACCCAAAACACCUUUUAUGUUUGCUUAGGGUAUAUUUUUUCAGUGUCUGAAAGUCAAAGGUAUUCCUGUCACAACUGUAAACAAACUUAUCCUAAAUGUGUUAAAACAUAUUCUUGGGUACUCUAUUUAUGUAUCUUUCAUGCCUUGAAAAUCUGAAGGUUAAUCCAAACUCACAUGUUUUAGCAUAUUUGAGAAAAAAAAACUACCUUCAAUAUCAGCCUUUUAAAUUUCAUGAAGAUUUUGGUGAGGAAUAAUAGUAUAUAGUUUAAGUAUUGACAAAACUUUGAAAGUUUCUUUCUUUAAAAUGGGAAAUACUCAAUAUCUAAAUCCAGGUCAGGCAUGGGAUAUCAGUAUUUAACAUUGGAUGUUUUAUGUUUUAUAUUUAUAAUGUUCAAAAUGCAAGCAUAACAUUUAAUAUUUGUCCACAUGGUUUUACAAAAGUAAAUCUUAAAUUACUAAGCUUUUCCCAUAUGUUCUCGUACUUUCUCAAAUCCCUAUAAAGAAUUACUUGUUAUCUAUUAAAAAUCUCCUUUACCCAAAUCUGUAUUAUGGUUUCGCCAGACAAAUAUUAUGUGAUGUAGCCCAGAAAAUCCACACCUUUUGUCCUUUUUAUGUUUUAAUUUGAAUAAUCAUGUGCUUAGUCCCUUGGAUUACUGCCACAUCAGUUUAACACGAUAUCAGCACAUUCCCUUGUCAUCAUCAAGGUGUUGGCUCAGAUUUAUUCUUAAUUGGAUGUUUAAAGCAUGUACUACCUUGUUACAGUUGGUUUAGUGUAGUGGAUUAUUGACAUGACAUCAUGAGAAGAUGUGUAAUUUUAUACCACAUUUAUAAAACAUGAUUUUGUUUUCUACCCUUCAAGGUAAACAUUAAAAAUAAGGUGGUACUUGUGUACUUGUACAUAAAACCAAAAUUAUAGUUGGGAAAAAAAUAAAUUUAUAUAUGAAAAUGUCAAAAUCAUUUUAAAAGUAUUAUUUUCAAAUAAAAUGGAGAAGCUGGUGAAAAGUCAUAUUGGCAAUUUUUAUGUAGUUUAAGUGGAAUUAAGCAGAGGGAGAUGCUUUUGGGUUUUUAAUAUGCCACUUCUGAGUGAAAACAUCUCGUGGAGUCAUUGUGUUCAGCUCUGAGAAGAACAAAGAUUCAUAGUUCUGUACAUGUGGCUGGAUUUAAAUAUCCUGUUUUUGAUACUAAUUUUGAAAGUCAUGUAACUUCUUUUGAUAUCUGGGCAAAAGUAACCAUAUGCUAUAAGCAUUUGAAUAUGUUUAAUUUUAUCAUAAUAGCAUCUGUAAAAGUACAUCUUACACAUUAUAUAGAGGGUUCUUGUUUGAAAUUUUCAGUUCUCUUUAUCUUCCCAGUACCUCUUGGUCCUCAUAAUGGGCAAAGGAUACAACGAAGGCAGGUUGUAUAGGGGUUAUAGUGGGGAAGUGGAUAGGGGAUUCAUUUUCUUAUGUGACAUUUUGCCUUAAGAAUAUAAAAGUGCUUUAGCACUGAUGGCUGGCAUUUUUAAUAUAGGCAGUGAAAGUGACUUUAGAAGCAUGGGAUGAAAUAGAGGGAAGAAGAGUUUUUAUUUUCUGGCCUUUAAAAAGUGCCUAGUAGGUCAUUUGAGACCCAGAGAAAUGCACAGAGCUUGAGCAAAGGCAUGAAGUCCCUGACAUUGUUUUCCUUUUUGUCUCAGCAUAUAGUAUUAAGAUGCCUAGAAAUAGGACUCUAUUGUUCCCUCUUGUAUAGGCACUUUACAUUUCUUGUCACUACAGCAACCACAUACAGUACAGACAACCUCCAAACCUGUUUAUAUUAGUGUAAAUAGAAAAUCUAUAGACAACUUUCUAGUUUUCUCUGGAGGCAUUUUUGGGAAUGUACGUGUAAUAGGCUCUGCUUUGUAUACAGGAGAUAAUACCACAUCAUCGGUUAUCUCCAAACUCCAGUCUUCUCUCAACUGCCCAGUUGUAUGUUGUCAUCAAUCACUUUUUCAAGGCUGGGUAGAGACAAGUUUCUCCUCGUAACUUUGACCUCUCCCACUCUCCAAAUGUAAUCUGGACCUCAUUGCUUUCAAGGUCAGCUUCCCCAUAGCUCAGGUAUCCUUUGCUCUCCUGUAUCUUCAUUUACUAUUAGUGAAGAGAUCUCUGUCCUGGAGGUUAUUCUAAACUUUCUUUGUAACUAUUGUUAUAGACAAUGGUUUCCAAACCAGUGGUUUCUAUGUAGCUUUUCUAGUUCCUUGCUAUCUUCUCACCACUGGCUUGAGGUAGUGAUUUGGACUUUGCUCAUUAGAGAGCAUUAUCAGAGAUGUGGAGUCCAUCAGAAGACCAGCUUGCAGUGUGUAUAGCAUAUAGAUGCCAAUAUUAGAAUUCUUUAAAUUAUAUUUAACAUUUUCAUGCUUCUUAAUUUAACUUCACAUGUUGGGAAGUAGAUUCAGAAAGAUAGGAGAAAUACCCAGACUCUACCACUUCCGUGAGCUACUAGUUAGGCAUGGGCAGGAUUAAGUUUUAUGUGUAUUAUCUUCCCACUACCAAGAAUGGUUAUGUUUCACAGAAUACCAGUUCAGUUUGAUUUGGAAAAAGAUGCCAAACCAAAUUUAUAUGUAGUCUAUAAUCUAAGGGCAUUCUUGAAACUAUUGCCCACAUCCCAUUUUUUUUUUCAUGUUUACUUACAAAACAGAGAUAAACAUUAGAUGUCUAAAGGAGUUAGUAAUGAAAAGCCUAUCCUUAAAAAAUAAACCUGUUGAAAUGGGCUUUAAAGACAUCGAAAUAAUCACUUGUCAUGCAUUGACUGUAAAUGCAGAUAGAGAAAUAUGUCUUUGAAGCUCCACUUACACAAAAAUAAAACUUGUAUAUCAUGCUCCCUCAAAGAAUGUGCGAUAGAUUAUUUUAAGACCAUGAUAAUAGAGUAAAAAGGAAAGAAAGCCAGAAAUUACAAUUUUGGAUGCUAAAAAGUAACUUUCUAGUUAACCCUAAAGUCCUGUCAGAUUGUGAAGAAAUGUUCCAGGAUACACUUGGAUUAGUUAUGCAGUAUUUCUUAUCAAUGUCUAGCCCUUGUGUAUUGUUCUGAAAACUAAAGUUUAAAUCUUUAUGCUGUUGCUUGCUAGAUAUCCUGUUCUUUGGUAGAAAAUUCCCAUAGUCUGUACUCAAGAAGUGCCUAAAAAUGGAUUUGUGUUGAUUUUAAGCCCAUCUAAUAAAUUAUAUGUAUUUUCUAUGGUA